GGAGCGAGGCCAGGGUAGGGUGAGCGGCCUCCGAAGCGGAGCGGGGCUCUGAGGAGACACUUUUUUUUUCCUCCCUCCUUCCCUCCUCUCCUCCUCCCUUCCCUUCCCCUCUCCUCCCCUCUCUCCUCCUUCCCCCCUCGGUCCGCCGGAGCCUGCUGGGGCGAGCGGUUGGUAUUGCAGGCGCUUGCUCUCCGGGGCCGCCCGGCGGGUAGCUGGCGGGGGGAGGAGGCAGGAACCGCGAUGGCGCCUCAGAAGCACGGCGGUGGGGGAGGGGGCGGCUCGGGGCCCAGCGCGGGGUCCGGGGGAGGCGGCUUCGGGGGUUCGGCGGCGGUGGCGGCGGCGACGGCUUCGGGCGGCAAAUCCGGCGGCGGGAGCUGUGGAGGGGGUGGCAGUUACUCGGCCUCCUCCUCCUCCUCCGCGGCGGCAGCGGCGGGGGCUGCGGUGUUACCGGUGAAGAAGCCGAAAAUGGAGCACGUCCAGGCUGACCACGAGCUUUUCCUCCAGGCCUUUGAGAAUCAUGUUUGGAUUUUGUUUCCUAUUACCUAGAGCCAACACAGAUCUAUAGAUUUCUUCGAACUCGGAAUCUCAUAGCACCAAUAUUUUUGCACAGAACUCUUACUUACAUGUCUCAUCGAAACUCCAGAACAAACAUCAAAAGGAAAACAUUUAAAGUUGAUGAUAUGUUAUCAAAAGUAGAGAAAAUGAAAGGAGAGCAAGAAUCUCAUAGCUUGUCAGCUCAUUUGCAGCUUACGUUUACUGGUUUCUUCCACAAAAAUGAUAAGCCAUCACCAAACUCAGAAAAUGAACAAAAUUCUGUUACCCUGGAAGUCCUGCUUGUGAAAGUUUGCCACAAAAAAAGAAAGGAUGUAAGUUGUCCAAUAAGGCAAGUUCCCACAGGUAAAAAGCAGGUGCCUUUGAAUCCUGACCUCAAUCAAACAAAACCCGGAAAUUUCCCGUCCCUUGCAGUUUCCAGUAAUGAAUUUGAACCUAGUAACAGCCAUAUGGUGAAGUCUUACUCGUUGCUAUUUAGAGUGACUCGUCCAGGAAGAAGAGAGUUUAAUGGAAUGAUUAAUGGAGAAACCAAUGAAAAUAUUGAUGUCAAUGAAGAGCUUCCAGCCAGAAGAAAACGAAAUCGUGAGGAUGGGGAAAAGACAUUUGUUGCACAAAUGACAGUAUUUGAUAAAAACAGGCGCUUACAGCUUUUAGAUGGGGAAUAUGAAGUAGCCAUGCAGGAAAUGGAAGAAUGUCCAAUAAGCAAGAAAAGAGCAACAUGGGAGACUAUUCUUGAUGGGAAGAGGCUGCCUCCAUUCGAAACAUUUUCUCAGGGACCUACGUUGCAGUUCACUCUUCGUUGGACAGGAGAGACCAAUGAUAAAUCUACGGCUCCUAUUGCCAAACCUCUUGCCACUAGAAAUUCAGAGAGUCUCCAUCAGGAAAACAAGCCUGGUUCAGUUAAACCUACUCAAACUAUUGCUGUUAAAGAAUCAUUGACUACAGAUCUACAAACAAGAAAAGAAAAGGAUACUCCAAAUGAAAACCGACAAAAAUUAAGAAUAUUUUAUCAGUUUCUCUAUAACAACAAUACAAGGCAACAAACUGAAGCAAGAGAUGACCUGCAUUGCCCUUGGUGUACUCUGAACUGCCGCAAACUUUAUAGUUUACUCAAGCAUCUUAAACUCUGCCAUAGCAGAUUUAUCUUCAACUAUGUUUAUCAUCCAAAAGGUGCUAGGAUAGAUGUUUCUAUCAAUGAGUGUUAUGAUGGCUCCUAUGCAGGAAAUCCUCAGGAUAUUCAUCGCCAACCUGGAUUUGCUUUUAGUCGCAACGGACCAGUUAAGAGAACACCUAUCACACAUAUUCUUGUGUGCAGGCCAAAACGAACAAAAGCAAGCAUGUCUGAAUUUCUUGAAUCUGAAGAUGGGGAAGUAGAACAGCAAAGAACAUAUAGUAGUGGCCACAAUCGUCUGUAUUUCCAUAGUGAUACCUGCUUACCUCUCCGUCCACAAGAAAUGGAAGUAGAUAGUGAAGAUGAAAAGGAUCCUGAAUGGCUAAGAGAAAAAACCAUUACACAAAUUGAAGAGUUUUCUGAUGUUAAUGAAGGAGAGAAAGAAGUGAUGAAACUCUGGAAUCUCCAUGUCAUGAAGCAUGGGUUUAUUGCUGACAAUCAAAUGAAUCAUGCCUGUAUGCUGUUUGUAGAAAAUUAUGGACAGAAAAUAAUUAAGAAGAAUUUAUGUCGAAACUUCAUGCUUCAUCUAGUCAGCAUGCAUGACUUUAAUCUUAUUAGCAUAAUGUCAAUAGAUAAAGCUGUUACCAAGCUCCGUGAAAUGCAGCAAAAAUUAGAAAAGGGGGAAUCUGCUUCCCCUGCAAACGAAGAAAUAACUGAAGAACAAAAUGGGACAGCAAAUGGAUUUAGUGAAAUUAACUCAAAAGAGAAAGCUUUGGAAACAGAUAGUGUCUCAGGGGUUUCAAAACAGAGCAAAAAACAAAAACUCUGAAAAGCUCUAACCCCAUGUUAUGGACAAACACUGAAAUUACAUUUUAGGGAAUUCAUCCUCUAAGAAUUAUGUUUUUGUUUUUAAUCAUAUGUUCCAAACAGGCACUGUUAGAUGAAGUAAAUGAUUUCAACAAGGAUAUUUGUAUCAGGGUUCUACUUCACUUCAUUAUGCAGCAUUACAUGUAUAUCACUUUUAUUGAUGUCAUUAAAACAUUCUGUACUUUAAGCAUGAAAAGCAAUAUUUCAAAGUAUUUUUAAACUCAACAAAUGUCAUCAAAUAUGUUGAAUUGAUCUAGAAAUUAUUUCAUAUAUAAAUCAGAAUUUUUUUGCAUUUAUGAACGGCUGUUUUUCUACUUUGUAAUUGUGAGACAUUUUCUUGGGGAGGGAAAAUUGGAAUGGUUCCCUUUUUUAGAAAUUGAAGUGGUCUUCAUAUGUCAACUACAGAAAAGGAAAAAAAUAGAAAUUGAAGGAUUUUUAUGAAAUUAUAUUGCAUUACUAUUUGCAGUCAAACUUUGAUCCUUGUUUUUGAAAUCAUUUGUCAAUUCGGAAUGAAAAAUUAUAAUGUAAUUUUACAUUACAUAAGUUCCUUUUACAAUUAAAAAAUAGCACUUCUUCAUCUUAUGCCUGUUUGAGAAGAUAUUAAAUUUUCACAUUGUUGACAGUGAAAUGCUAUGUUGGUUUAUAAGAUUACAGACCAUUUGUUUUCAUGUGGAUAAUUUUAGUGCAUUGCUCACCCGGUAUGUUUUUUUUUUUUAACUUGAACAUUUUGCUUGUUUUGUUUUUCUUUUUUAAUUAGAUAAUCACACGGAAAAUUAAGCUGUUCAUAUCUUUAAAUUAGGAUUGCAAACCAAGGAAAGAACGCAUUUGAGAUUUUAAGAUGUCACUUAUAAGGGGAGAAGUGUUCUUAAAAAGUCAACCAGAAAACUGUUAUGCCUUUUAUUUGUUUGCAAGGAUGUCUUUGUAAUGUGUUUCAUGAAUAGAAUAUCCAAUAGAGAUAAGCUGACUUGAAUCAUUUUGAGCAAUUUUGCCCUGUGUUAUAUGUGUUUCACGCACAUAUUUGCAGUUGGAUUUUCUCCAACAGAAAGUGGAUUCACUACUGGCACAUUAACAAGCACCAAUAGGUUUUUAUUCCAACUCCGAGCACUGUGGUUGAGUAACAUCACCUCAAUUUUUUAUUAUCCUUAAAGAUAUUGCAUUUUCAUAUUCUUUAUUUAUAAAGGAUCAAUGCUGCUGUAAAUACAGGUAUUUUUAAUUUUAAAAUUUCAUUCCACCACCAUCAGAUGCAGUUCCCUAUUUUGUUUAAUGAAGGGAUAUAUAAGCUUUCUAAUGGUGUCUUCAGAAAUUUAUAAAAUGUAAAUACUGAUUUGACUGGUCUUUAAGAUGUGUUUAACUGUGAGGCUAUUUAACGAAUAGUGUGGAUGUGAUUUGUCAUCCAGUAUUAAGUUCUUAGUCAUUGAUUUUUGUGUUUAAAAAAAAAUAGGAAAGAGGGAAACUGCAGCUUUCAUUACAGAUUCCUUGAUUGGUAAGCUCUCCAAAUGAUGAGUUCUAGUAAACUCUGAUUUUUGCCUCUGGAUAGUAGAUCUCGAGCGUUUAUCUCGGGCUUUAAUUUGCUAAAGCUGUGCACAUAUGUAAAAAAAAAAAAAAAAAGAUUAUUUUAGGGGAGAUGUAGGUGUAGAAUUAUUGCUUAUGUCAUUUCUUAAGCAGUUAUGCUCUUAAUGCUUAAAAGAAGGCUAGCAUUGUUUGCACAAAAAGUUGGUGAUUCCCACCCCAAAUAGUAAUAAAAUUACUUCUGUUGAGUAAACUUUUUAUGUCAUCGUAAAAGCUGAAAAAAUCCCUUUGUUUCUAUUUAUAAAAAAAGUGCUUUUCUAUAUGUACCCUUGAUAACAGAUUUUGAAGAAAUCCUGUAAGAUGAUAAAGCAUUUGAAUGGUACAGUAGAUGUAAAAAAAAUUCAGUUUAAAAGAACAUUUGUUUUUACAUUAAAUGUUUAUUUGAAAUCAAAUGAUUUUGUACAUAAAGUUCAAUAAUAUAAAAGCUG